UUCUCCCUCAUUUUAUUCCAAAAUAUUAGAAGUGCAGAGGAGAGAAAAAGAAGGAGAAAAAAAAUACCGUGCCUCAAAAGAAGGUGUGUUUUGGAUGUUGUGCCAUGUGAAAUCAAAUUUUAUAAUGUUCAUGAAAGAUGUUAGGUUAAGCAUUCAUUGGAGAAUCAUCUUUGGCUUUUAUAUUUUAGUAAUUUAAAAAAUUUAAUUUUGCUAAAUUUUUUGUGAACCAAUUCUCCGGAAAUACUAUUGUUGAAUAUAAAUACUUGCAAUUUUCAUUUUUUCCAUUCCCUUCAGAUAGUCUGAAUUUCAGAAAGUUUCAGUAUUUUGAAUAUUUUGCAGAAAAUAUUUAUUUAUUUGUAUAGACAGUAUCAAGAGCAUCUAAUUAAGUCACCAAAUGAAGAUCAGGUUGUAAAAAUUAUGAAUAAAAAUUGGUGCCUUAUUUAAUAAUCUCUAUACUUAGUACACUAUAAAGUCCCACUAAUACAAUGGUCUUAAAAAUGACUAAAAAGAACUUCUCUGUCAGUAAAUAUCCGCUGACCCUGGAAUUCCUCAAAAAUAUGGGUUUGUGAGCUAGACCCCCUGCAAAUAUAUAAAAGUGAUCCAGACUAAUGAUUAUGUGUUGUAAUCUAAGAAUACUCAUUCCUACAGUCCUAAGAAAUAAGUAGGAAGAUUAGAUUUUCUAUGCUUCUUCUUAUGCUUCUAAAAGAUUCAUGAACAUGACUUUUCCAGGAUGAUUGUUGGCCAAAAUUAUUUUUUUUCCUUUCCUGACCUUAUUGUCGUUAUUUAAAGUAUAAGGUAGAUUAGCUUUGCUCUCCAACAGGUCUAGAUUCAAGUUAUAGACAAACUCAAACAAUGCAGUUACCUCUCUGAGUCUUAUUCUUGUCACCUGUCACAUAGGGCAGUGAUAUCUACCUACCUCACAGGGGUGUAUGGGGAAAAAAACAAGAUCUUCGUAAAAUGCCAAGCACAAGUGCUCAAUAAAUGAGGACAAUGGUGAUGGCGAUGGUGGUGGUAAAGCCAUCAUCAUCAUUAGAUCAGGCAAAUAGAAUUGUUUCCAAUAAUUUAGUUACUAUUGAGCCCAAUUUUAUCCUGUGUUCUGACCUCACUCAAAUACUUUGUUUCCAUGGAAUGUAAUACAUGAUUAACAGGAACGAAUGAUCCGCCAAACAUUGUAAUCUCCUUGGAAGUGUUCUAGUUUGUAGAGAUCAUGGAGAUCAUUUAGGGCCUGUCACUCUGGCAUGCUGCUAUCCUGGAAGAGAUGUUUGAGGAUUGUGGCUGUUUUGCUUUUACUACAAAUUUCUUCAUAUCUUAGGCUUUAGCAUUUGAGGAGACUUUUCCGUGAGGGUCAAAUUAUGCCUGCAGGUAGGAGGCUUUUAAAAGUGCACUCAGUGUUUUAAUUUCUUUAGCUAAUGCUUUUGCAAUAAUAAAAAUGUCUUUCUACUUUCAGCAGAAGAGUAUUAUAUUUAGAUUUUCUGAAUUUUAAAGCAGUUACCAAAAGCUACGCUAAGUUUUUCAAAGGAAUUUAAAAGGCAUAAAUGAUCCUUUACAAAAUAGUGACUAAAGGCCGACCUUUCUAAAUGAAAAAAUAACUGAAUCUUAUUCUCAAUUCCUCUUCUGUUUCCUCGCCCUCCUUCCAAAACUGGUUUUUUCUUGAGGUGACCCCAAGGCCUUGGCAUGGAAAUUUAGAGGAGAUUACCACAUAAAAAUAGAUACCAUUAGCUAAUAUAAGUCAUGUACAGAAGAAAAGAUCUUUUGUGUCUCUUGUAUCCCUAAUGCUUCCCACAAUACCUAGCACUUAGUAGGUAUUCAGUAAUAUUUGGUAAGUGAAGGACUUAAAAUUUCAAAAUUCUGGCUAAAUUAUGCAUCUCAUGUAAAGCUGUAGCAGUUGCACUUUGAAAAUCCAAUAACAUGCAAAAUCUCAGGGAAAAUUCCUAACGUGAAAAAUCUCGGGACAAGAUAAAGGAGGCAGUAUCAUCUUUGUGUCUCUACUUCUGAAGUUCAGUCUUACUAAAACACCUGGUCUAUCACUACUGACUCUAAAUCUUAUCUUUAUGAGCUAUUUUGAUUGACUGACAUAACCCUAAAAACUAAUGCAUUUAACAGUCCCGAAGAACAAGUCUAAGGAGAUGUACUCAUUUAAUUUUGGAAUGAUGAGAAAAUUUUUCCCCAAAUGCUCAACUGGUAGAGGGGAGGGAAGAAGAAUAGAAUAUACAAACCAACUUAGUCUUGCAAAUGUAAACCUCAGUAUUCUCCUUAAGUCACAAAGGCACAAAUAAAUAUACAUGUAACCAUUUUAAAACCAUUUACAGUUAAGGAUGUGAACAUUGAUUUGACUCUAAAAUAUUUUUGUAUUGCUCUAAGUACUGUAUCCUACACUUUAGAGGGGAAAGAUUUUGCCAGAGUUAGUUGGCAAAGGCAUUUGUGUUGGCUUGAAAAACCAUAAGCUAAUCACUUAUUUAGUCCGUUAAAAACAACUUGAUUAAUGUUUGGUAAGAAAUUCUGACUAAAAUUCUCCAUUAUAUGCUUCCAAAUACAAUAGAACUUUGAAGAUCAUAAGCAAGUCACAGUCAUAUUUGGCUAUUACUGUUUGUUAUAAAACAAUACCACAGUAUGUCAAAUGGUCUGUGUACCAUAUUUUCGUACCCCUACCUCAUCCUAAGCCAGCAUGUGUAGUUAACUUUAUAAUCUUGUUUACUUUCACAUUUUCUCUGGGACAGCUAGAAACUUUAAUGUGAAGAUGACAUUAUACACUGUAGCAGAUUCCCUCAAUAUCCAGGCUUUUCUCCUCUCUGCUGGCUACAGAUAAUGUGAGGGCCCUGCCCAUAUUUUCCCACUGUGUUCCUUCUUUUAGUGCAUGCUGGAGGCUUCUUACUUCAAGCACUGUGACUCUGUCUGAGGGCUUUAUCAGGCCUUGGGAGCCUGCCUGACCCAUGUAGGGUAGGCCAGAAGGGCCUGGAAGUAAACACCCCUGGAGCAAUACCUUACCCAAUAAUAUAUGAAAGUUGGUGAGUAAAUACCCCACUUUCUCACAUCUUAGGUGAGGCAACUUUUGAGGUAUGAACCAUACAUUCCUCCAGAGGUACCCAAUGGAACCGAGCUCCAGCUGCUCAUAGUGGUAACCUACCUGCUCAUUAACAUUGACUUUUUUCCCUUCUCUGUCUCACUUCUCCACUCCUUUACCAGGAGUUACCUCCCAAAUAAACUAAUUGAAUGAAUUCUUGUCCAGGGUCUGCUUUUGGGAGAACCCAGUCUACCAUAAACUUUUUGGCUAUUUCAGUAAAUGCAGUAUAAGUUAUACUGCAGUAAACUAAGUAUAGCUUAUACUUAGCCAAGUGGACUAUAGAUGCCAUUCUAGCCAAAAAGUAAAUCAUGAAUGGAAUUCUUGCUUUCCACAGUGCAGAACAGAAUUUUGUCUGUAGCUAAUACUGUUUCAUUGGUGUCUUGGUGUCUUGUUUAACUUGUAUCUUAUUGGUCAUAACUGGAUCCUAAAUUCUCAUCGCCUUUUUUGGAAACUGUCAUGGGACAUGGAGGGAGAUAUCAGUGAAGAUUUGGUGUGACUCCAGAACAAUGAGGGUUUAGUGUGAUCCCAUAAUUAGAGAAAUAGCACAAAGAACAUAUUCUGCUCAUGUUAUGUAAAGAGGUUCUGGAAAGUGGUUCAAACACAUGCUCAGUGAAGAUAAUGCUGGGCCCUUUAUUUUCCUGCUGGGUGUUCCUAUCCCCUCCACAGGUUGGGUCACCAUUUAUUUAUCAGUGAUUUUCUAAUCCAUACCGCCAGGCCAGACCUCUCCUGAGAACUCCAGUCCCAGAUAUCUAACUGCCCACAAGGCACUUGAAGAUUUGUUUGCACCACAAGUCCAACAAGUCCCAAAUGGUACUCAUUAUCUUCCCCCAAACCCUCCCCUCUUCCUGCGAAUGGCACAACCCAGUGGCCCCAUCAGAAAACUUUGAAGUAGCCUUGAGGAUCUGUCCUUCUCACUUCAUCAACAGUCCCAUCUAAUCAGUCUCCAAGUCUUACAAAUUUAAUUUCCUAACAAUCUCUACAAACUUCUCUCCAUUCUCCUUGUCAUCACUGCAUUUCCAAAACACCGUCAUCUAUUUCACUCAACACCGGCCUCCUAGUGCCCCUCCCUGUAUCUAGUCAUGCCCCUCUUGUAGCAUUCUCCACACUUCAGCCUGAAAACAUCUGCUCACACUUUUCUCUGGUUAAAAUGCUCCAAUGGCUUUAGGUAAAAUCCAAAAUCCUUAUCCUGGUUGAAAAUCCUCCCACCACUCCACCUUAACUGUGUCUUCUGCAUCAUGCCUUCUUAUUUUGUUCCCACUACUCCCAGUCCUCUAGUUCUUUAGGGAGAUCUUGCUCUCUCUCACCUCCUGCCACUUGCAUUUUGGAAUCUCUUCUACCUAAAACCAUAUUCUCCAGACUCUCAACCUGGCUAACUGCUUCUUUCCCUUUAGAACUUAGCUACUAUGUUCAUUCCUUGAGAAAAAGCAUUACUGGACCCCCUUACUAGGAAAAGUGCCCUUCCCUGGAUCCCCACAAUAGCCUGGGCUUCCUUAGCCAUAUCGCUCUCCCACUAAAAGCUCUAUUUCUUAGUGUUUCAUGUUCACCAGACUGCCUUCAGUGCCAGCUACUGAAGUAUCUGUUGUAUGAAUAAUGAGCUGAAAUCAGGUUCCUUACUAGCUGAUGAUCAUGGGCAAGUCACCUAACUUAUCUGAACUUCAGUUUUCUCAUCAAAGUGGAAACAAUAUUCAAGCACAGGGUGAUUGAGAGGAGUUGAUGAAAUUAUGGAUCUGGGGUUCCUGACACCUAAGUUGGUGCUCAAUACAUAGAAGUUAUUUUGGAUUCAGCAAGGUAGAACUAGGCUUGCCUUGCCUCAUGAUGUUUUGAGACAGUAAAGGCUACAUCCUGGAAGGUGUAAGUUAAAGGGGCACUUUGAUGUAGCAGCUCUGGGAGGAACCCAGAGGGAGGAAAGUAUCAUUUAGCUAAAAGCUAAAAGGUCUUUUAAAACCUUUCAAGAGGUGUGUUUUUGGAAAUGCAAGUGAUGUAACUACAUAUAAUGGCAUCUAAUUCCCUCACAGUUUCUUCCAAACAGUCUUUCUCCUUGAGUUUCAAUAUCUGCAUUCCCUGGGUUAAUGCCAUGAAUCCAAUUUCUAAACUGAGAUUUUUUUCCAAGAGUUCUGCCUUAAUUAGUUAUUCCCCGCUCCUCCGUGGUUUUUUCUUUCCCCCUUCUCCACGAGUACUGUCAUCAACCUGAAAUGGCACCAUUAAGCACCUAAUCUUUGAGCCUCCGGGGAACUGUCAUCAAAAUGCUCAGGAACCGAGAUGUACAUUUACAGGCAAUGUAACUGGGUAGAGGCAAGCACUAAACAAGUUCCUCAGCUUGCACUGGUGAAUGAUGAAGGCAGAGAAUUUCUUAGCUUUUACUAGAGAGGUGAAUUAAGUACAUAAUUGGGGUGGAAAUUGGGAUAAUAGCACCUCAGGGAGCUGUCUGCACAUUUUAAGGGCUUUUAGGUAUUUAGUAAGUUACUGCUUUGACGCACUUACCUAAUAGUCCAUAGCAAAACAGUUUUCAAGUUCACUGGGCCAGAGGUGCCCUGCCCCACUCUAAACAUACAAAGUGUAUAAAUUCCUUUUUUUCCUAUAUAUCCUAACAAUUUUGGAAUACAUAGUCACUUGUAAGUAACAGUCAGUAUACUCAGAAAAAUAGGCAAAAUGGUGGUUAAUGGUGUUGUCUAUGUUGGAGUCCCACCUCAUUUUCUUGGAUCAGCUUGAAUAGAUAAAUUCAUAAAUAUGUAUUCUUAGCUGCAAAAUUCUUUAAGUAGUUGCCUUUUUACUUCCAAAAGCAUGAAGGACUUUAUUUAUCUGUUUAUUUUAUUUCUCAGUGCUCUUAUCAAGUCUUUAAAUUUCUUCAUGGAGAAAACAGCAAUUAGGCAAUAGAUGUUCCUAUGUCAUCUCAAUCAGCAGUAGCAAAAGUUGUUAAGUUGGGCAGUGUGCUGGGCACCGACUGCAUGAUUCCAUGCCUUCCAUCCCUGCUAAAGUCCCCCUUGAGAAAGGAGAUGUGCGCUGUGGAUGCAGAGCUGAAGCCAUGCCACUAACUGCAGCCACUAAGCAAUUUUGGGCUGGGAUAGAAAUACCCUAGGGAAAAAGAGAUGAAUGACUUCAGCUCUUCACAAGGUGGGUCUUCAAAUACUCCAAUCCAGAGUUUUCUACAUCAAUGAACUCAGCACUUAUUAAACAUAUUAUAUACAUUAUCACAUUUAAUCCUUACAACAACCCAUUAUCCUGCUUUCACAAAUGAGAGUCCAGGAUUUCAAGGUUCAUCAAUUGCUCAAAUCACAGCUGGCCAAUGAAAGAGAUUUGAAUUCUGGAUGUGGUUAAAACUCAGACCUUGAUACUGCUAUCUGUAUAUUCUGCCAGGUAAUCUGGAAAAUGUGUGCUUCAAAAGCCUAGAAACUUCUAAUGUGGACAAAAUUUAGAUUCCUGGAUGCUCGGAAUAACAGUUCAGAAGUCAUAUUUUUCAUGGUCUGGGGACAAGAAAAACUCUUACGACUUUGUAAAUAUUGAUGGAUUGUUUUCUCUAAGGCAUUUCACAUAUUAGAAGAUUUGAAGUUGAAGAUUUUUCAGGUCAUAAUAUGAUGUUGCUAAUUUUGUUCCUCGUGAUAAUUUGUUCCCAUAUUUCUGUGAACCAAGAUUCCGGCCCUGAGUAUGCAGAUGUUGUGUUUUUGGUGGACAGCUCUGAUCGCCUGGGAUCCAAGUCCUUCCCAUUUGUGAAAAUGUUCAUCACCAAAAUGAUCAGCAGUCUCCCCAUAGAGGCCGACAAAUACCGUGUGGCCCUGGCCCAGUACAGUGAUAAACUUCACAGUGAAUUCCACCUGAGCACCUUCAAAGGCAGGAGCCCCAUGCUGAACCACCUAAGGAAGAACUUUGGAUUCAUUGGCGGGUCCCUGCAGAUAGGAAAGGCUCUUCAGGAGGCUCACAGGACUUAUUUCUCUGCACCCGCAAAUGGGAGAGACAAGAAACAGUUUCCCCCAAUUCUAGUGGUCCUGGCUUCAUCUGAGUCUGAGGAUAAUGUGGAAGAGGCAUCAAAGGCCCUGCGGAAAGACGGAGUGAAAAUCAUCUCUGUAGGGGUGCAGAAAGCUUCUGAGGAAAACCUGAAGGCCAUGGCCACGUCUCAGUUUCAUUUCAACCUUCGGACAGUCAGAGACCUCAGCAUGUUUUCCCAAAACAUGACACACAUCAUCAAGGAUGUAAUAAAGUACAAGGAGGGAGCAGUUGAUGACAUCUUUGUAGAAGCUUGCCAAGGCCCUUCUAUGGCCGAUGUUGUGUUCCUAUUGGAUAUGUCAAUCAAUGGAAGUGAGGAGAACUUUGACUAUCUUAAAGGAUUCUUGGAAGAAAGUGUAUCUGCCCUUGACAUAAAGGAAAAUUGCAUGAGGGUUGGCCUUGUGGCCUAUAGCAAUGAGACAAAAGUGAUAAAUUCACUGAGCAUGGGCAUAAAUAAGUCAGAGGUUCUCCAGCAUAUACAGAACCUUUCUCCCCGAACUGGGAAGGCCUAUACUGGAGCUGCCAUCAAAAAGCUCAGGAAGGAAGUUUUUAGUGCACGGAAUGGCAGUCGGAAGAAUCAGGGGGUGCCCCAGAUUGCCGUGCUGGUGACCCACCGAGAUUCAGAAGACAACGUGACAAAAGCAGCUGUUAACCUCCGACGGGAGGGUGUGACCAUCUUCACCCUGGGCAUAGAGGGCGCCAGCGACACCCAGUUGGAAAAGAUAGCAUCCCACCCUGCUGAGCAGUAUGUCUCCAAACUGAAGACCUUCGCUGACCUGGCUGCUCACAACCAGACAUUUCUGAAGAAGCUGCGGAACCAAAUAACACACACAGUCUCUGUCUUUUCAGAGAGGACUGAAACGCUCAAAUCUGGUUGUGUGGACACUGAGGAAGCAGACAUCUAUCUGCUUAUCGAUGGCUCAGGGAGCACCCAGGCCACAGAUUUCCAUGAAAUGAAGACGUUCCUGUCAGAGGUGGUAGGGAUGUUCAACAUUGCUCCCCAUAAGGUGCGGGUUGGGGCCGUUCAGUAUGCUGACAGCUGGGACUUGGAAUUUGAGAUCAAUAAAUACUCCAACAAGCAGGAUUUGGGAAAGGCCAUUGAGAAUAUCAGGCAGAUGGGUGGGAAUACAAACACAGGCGCAGCACUGAAUUUCACACUGAGUCUGUUGCAAAAAGCAAAGAAGCAGCGAGGAAACAAAGUUCCAUGCCACCUUGUUGUCCUGACAAAUGGCAUGUCCAAGGAUAGCAUCUUGGAGCCUGCAAACAGACUGAGAGAAGAGCACAUCCGAGUUUAUGCUAUCGGGAUCAAGGAGGCCAACCAAACACAGCUGAGAGAAAUUGCAGGAGAGGAAAAGAGAGUGUAUUACGUGCAUGACUUUGAUGCAUUGAAAGACAUAAGAAACCAAGUUGUUCAAGAAAUCUGUACUGAAGAAGCUUGCAAAGAGAUGAAAGCUGACAUCAUGUUUCUGGUGGACAGUUCUGGAAGUAUAGGACCUGAAAACUUCAGCAAAAUGAAAACAUUUAUGAAAAACCUGGUGAGCAAGUCUCAGAUUGGACCAGAUCGGGUGCAAAUUGGUGUAGUCCAGUUCAGCGACAUCAAUAAGGAAGAGUUUCAGCUCAACAGAUUCAUGUCCCAAAGCGACAUUUCAAAUGCAAUAGACCAAAUGGCUCACAUUGGACAAACCACCCUGACUGGUAGUGCCCUGAGCUUUGUGUCUCAGUACUUCAGCCCCACCAAGGGCGCCCGGCCCAACAUCAGAAAGUUUCUCAUCCUCAUCACGGAUGGUGAAGCUCAGGACAUAGUAAAGGAACCAGCAGUAGUGCUUCGGCAAGAAGGUGUAAUCAUCUAUUCUGUGGGAGUGUUUGGCUCCAAUGUCACCCAGCUUGAGGAGAUCAGUGGGAGGCCCGAGAUGGUUUUUUAUGUUGAGAAUUUUGACAUUCUGCAGCGCAUUGAAGAUGAUCUUGUUUUUGGAAUAUGCAGCCCCCGUGAAGAAUGCAAGCGGAUUGAAGUUUUAGACGUUGUGUUUGUCAUUGAUAGCUCUGGCAGUAUUGACUAUGAUGAGUAUAAUAUCAUGAAGGAUUUUAUGAUUGGCUUAGUGAAAAAAGCUGAUGUGGGCAAGAAUCAGGUCCGGUUUGGGGCUCUGAAGUAUGCUGAUGACCCAGAGGUGCUGUUUUAUCUGGAUGACUUUGGCACAAAACUGGAGGUAAUUUCAGUGCUCCAGAAUGACCAAGCCAUGGGUGGCAGUACUUAUACUGCUGAGGCACUGGGCUUCUCAGACCACAUGUUCACUGAAGCCCGGGGCAGCCGCCUGAACAAGGGGGUCCCCCAAGUCCUCAUUGUGAUCACCGAUGGGGAAUCCCAUGAUGCUGAUAAACUCAAUGCCACGGCAAAGGCCUUGCGGGACAAAGGCAUUCUUGUCCUGGCUGUGGGGAUUGAUGGUGCCAAUCCCGUGGAGCUGUUAGCCAUGGCAGGAUCAAGCGACAAGUACUUCUUCGUGGAGACUUUUGGAGGUCUGAAGGGAAUAUUUUCAGAUGUGACAGCCAGUGUCUGCAACUCUUCAAAAGUAGAUUGUGAAAUUGACAAAGUAGAUCUUGUUUUCCUUAUGGAUGGUUCAACUAGCAUUCAGCCAAAUGACUUCAAGAAAAUGAAGGAAUUUCUGGCAUCUGUUGUUCAAGACUUUGAUGUCAGCCUCAACAGAGUGCGAAUAGGAGCGGCCCAGUUUAGCGAUACCUAUCACCCGGAGUUUCCACUGGGAACUUUCAUAGGUGAAAAAGAGAUAUCAUUUCAGAUUGAAAACAUCAAGCAGAUCUUUGGAAACACACACAUCGGUGCUGCACUCAGGGAGGUGGAACAUUACUUCAGGCCAGACAUGGGCAGCAGGAUAAAUACAGGUACCCCACAGGUGCUGCUGGUCCUUACAGAUGGCCAGUCCCAAGACGAGGUGGCCCAGGCCGCGGAAGCCCUGAGACACAGAGGUAUCGACAUCUACUCCGUGGGCAUUGGGGAUGUGGAUGACCAGCAGCUCAUUCAGAUCACCGGGACUGCAGAGAAAAAACUGACAGUGCACAACUUCGAUGAACUGAAGAAGGUCAAUAAAAGGAUCGUUCGCAACAUCUGUACCACAGCGGGUGAAAGCAACUGUUUCGUGGAUGUUGUGGUGGGAUUUGAUGUCUCAACUCAGGAGAAAGGGCAGACUUUGCUUGAAGGUCAGCCUUGGAUGGAAACCUACCUUCAAGACAUCUUACGUGCCAUCAGCUCCCUCAAUGGAGUAAGCUGUGAGGUGGGCACAGAGACUCAGGUCAGUGUGGCUUUUCAAGUGACCAAUGCCAUGGAAAAAUAUUCUCCCAAGUUUGAGAUCUACAGUGAAAACAUACUGAAUAGCUUGAAGGAUAUAACAGUUAAAGGACCAUCUCUUCUCAAUGCAAACCUCUUGGAUUCUCUAUGGGAUACAUUUCAGAAUAAAUCAGCUGCUCGAGGAAAGGUGGUCCUUUUAUUUUCAGAUGGAUUGGAUGAUGAUGUUGAGAAACUUGAACAAAAAUCUGAUGAACUUAGAAAAGAAGGCCUGAAUGCCCUCAUAACUGUUGCUCUGGAUGGACCUGCUGAUUCAAGUGACUUGGCUGAUCUUCCCUAUAUUGAAUUUGGGAAAGGAUUUGAGUACAGGACACAGCUCUCUAUUGGCAUGAGAGAACUUGGAAGCCGGCUGUCAAAGCAGCUGGUCAAUGUUGCUGAAAGGACAUGCUGCUGUUUGUUCUGCAAGUGCAUUGGAGGAGAUGGCACAAUGGGAGAUCCUGGACCACCAGGGAAAAGGGGACCUCCAGGUUUUAAAGGCAGUGAAGGCUACCUGGGAGAGGAGGGAAUCGCUGGAGAAAGAGGAGCCCCUGGACCAGUGGGAGAGCAAGGUACUAAGGGAUGCUAUGGCACCAAAGGUCCUAAGGGAAACAGAGGACUAAAUGGACAGGAGGGAGAAGUUGGGGAAAAUGGAAUUGACGGAUUAAACGGAGAACAGGGUGAUAAUGGUCUUCCUGGAAGAAAAGGAGAAAAGGGAGAUGAGGGAUCUCAGGGAAGCCCAGGGAAGAGAGGGACUCCUGGUGACCGUGGAGCAAAGGGCCUGCGAGGGGAUCCCGGAGCUCCUGGAGUUGACAGUAGCAUAGAAGGACCCACAGGCUUGAAAGGAGAACGUGGAAGACAAGGCAGAAGAGGCUGGCCAGGCCCCCCCGGGACACCAGGCUCCAGAAGAAAGACAGCAGCUCAUGGCAGAAGGGGACAUACAGGCCCACAGGGAACAGCAGGCAUCCCAGGACCAGAUGGACUUGAAGGCUCCCUGGGACUUAAGGGCCCUCAGGGCCCAAGAGGAGAGGCUGGUGUGAAAGGAGAAAAAGGAGGUGUGGGAAGUAAAGGUCCCCAGGGGCCUCCAGGACCCGGAGGAGAGGCAGGGAAUCAAGGCCGUUUGGGAAGCCAAGGAAAUAAAGGAGAACCUGGAGAUCUGGGAGAAAAAGGAGCUGUUGGCUUUCCUGGUCCUCGUGGCUUGCAGGGCAAUGAUGGCAGUCCAGGUUAUGGUAGUGUCGGACGCAAGGGAGCAAAGGGACAAGAAGGAUUCCCUGGAGAAAGUGGACCUAAGGGUGAGAUUGGGGACCCUGGUGGUCCAGGAGAGACUGGGCUGAAGGGAGCUAGAGGCAAAAUGAUAUCUGCUGGGCUUCCAGGAGAGAUGGGAUCCCCUGGGGAACCAGGACCUCCUGGACGUAAGGGUGUGAAAGGAGCCAAAGGCUUGGCUUCAUUUUCUACAUGUGAGCUCAUUCAGUAUGUGCGAGACCGCAGUCCUGGCAGGCAUGGAAAACCGGAAUGCCCAGUGCACCCAACCGAGUUGGUGUUUGCCCUGGACCACUCCCGGGAUGUCACUGAGCAGGAAUUUGAGCGGAUGAAGGAGAUGAUGGCUUUCCUGGUGAGAGACAUUAAGGUCCGGGAGAACAGCUGCCCCGUGGGAGCGCACAUCGCCAUCCUCUCCUAUAACUCCCACGCCAGGCACCUUGUGCGCUUCUCAGACGCCUACAAGAAGAGUCAACUUCUCAGAGAAAUUGAAACUAUUCCUUAUGAGAGAUCCUCUGCCAGCAGGGAGAUUGGCAGAGCAAUGCGGUUUAUUUCCAGGAAUGUCUUCAAGCGGACGCUUCCGGGGGCACACACGAGAAAAAUCGCCACAUUUUUCAGCAGCGGUCAGUCCGCGGAUGCCCACUCCAUCACCACGGCUGCCAUGGAGUUCGGCGCGCUUGAAAUCAUUCCCGUGGUGAUCACUUUCAGCAACGUGCCCUCGGUCAGGCGCGCAUUUGCGAUUGACGACACUGGCACAUUUCAAGUAAUAGUGGUUCCCUCCGGGGCCGACUACAUACCAGCAUUAGAGAGACUCCAGCGGUGCACUUUCUGCUAUGAUGUGUGCAAGCCAGAUGCUUCUUGUGACCAAGCCAGACCACCCCCUGUGCAGUCUUACAUGGAUGCUGCUUUCCUUCUGGAUGCCUCCCGGAACAUGGGAAGUGCUGAAUUUGAAGACAUAAGAGCCUUCCUUGGAGCACUAUUAGAUCACUUUGAAAUCACCCCAGAGCCGGAGACUUCUGUCACUGGAGACCGGGUGGCCCUAUUGAGCCAUGCUCCCCCCGACUUCCUACCCAACACUCAGAAGAGUCCAGUUAGAGCUGAGUUCAAUCUUACCACCUACAGAAGUAAGCGCCUCAUGAAGAGGCAUGUGCACGAGUCAGUUAAACAACUAAAUGGAGAUGCUUUUAUUGGUCAUGCCUUACAGUGGACUCUGGACAAUGUAUUUUUAAGUACACCCAAUCUGAGAAGAAACAAAGUCAUAUUUGUGAUAUCUGCUGGGGAAACCAGCCACUUAGAUGGGGAAAUCUUAAAGAAGGAAUCCUUGCGAGCCAAAUGUCAGGGAUAUGCCUUAUUUGUGUUUUCCCUUGGCCCUAUUUGGGAUGACAAGGAACUGGAGGAUCUCGCCAGCCACCCUUUGGAUCACCACCUGGUCCAGCUUGGCCGAAUUCAUAAACCUGACCACAGUUAUGGUGUGAAGUUUGUGAAGUCCUUUAUAAACUCAAUCAGGCGUGCAAUCAACAAAUAUCCACCAAUAAACUUAAAAAUAAAGUGCAACAGACUUAACUCUAUAGAUCCAAAGCAGCCCCCACGACCAUUCCGAAGCUUUGUUCCUGGACCACUUAAAGCUACCCUCAAAGAAGAUGUAUUACAGAAGGCAAAAUUCUUUCAAGAUAAAAAAUAUCUUUCAAGAGUAGCAAGAAGUGGCAGAGAUGAUGCUAUUCAAAAUUUUAUGAGAAGCACCUCCCAUACCUUUAAGAAUGGAAGGAUGAUAGAAAGUGCUCCCAAACAACAUGAUUAAAAAAAUGCUUGAACAACUUAGCCUUAGGAAGCAUGGUAAGACUCUGGACUUAAAUAGUAACUAAAUCUGCUGCCAGAACUCAAGCAACAGUUUGUAGGUUAUCAGGUGACUUGACCCCCUGCAUUCAUUGGUAUUAAGAUAUAUCUUGUUCAUUUAUUUGACCACUCCUGACAAUUCCAGCACUCUACGACUGAUAUGUCGAAGAACUGUUUCAUUAGAAGACAGAAGAAUGAAAGAAGUGUUUUGAAAAGUCUAAUGGAGAUAUAAUUUGAAGGUAAAAUUUAUAUGAUGUAUGCAUAUGUGUACAUGGGUCAAUGUUAAUUCUUUUAUCUCUGUCCAGUUCAUUUUCUGCAAACCCAUCCUCCUUUCCUAAUUUAGUAAUGUCUAAUGCUCAUCUAUUUAGUCAAAGUUAUUUUUUAAUGUUUUAAGCUACUCCAAAAUUUAUCCUAGAAAUGGAUGCUGUUUAUAUGUCGUAUUUUUUUAAAACGUGACCUUCUAUUCCACUUAAACACACCACUGUGGGAGUUGUUUGCUUGGACUGAUGAGAAGAGGGUAAUUUUCUCCAUCUCUAAAUCCUCCUGAACUCACUGAAAAACUCAUUAAUUCCCGCAGAACAUAAAUUAUUGCUUUUGAGCUGGAAGUUUUCUCUUCAUUAGGAAGCUUACUGCCAUUUUGAUGGAGCUUGAAGCCCCCAUUUUGAUGGACUUCUAGUCUGUCUUUCCUGUUAUGGUCAUUUAUUAAUUUUCACUAAUCCAUAUAUUCUUUAGACAAGGAGAGUCAAGAAACUACUUGUCAUAGAUGAAGCUCUGAGUUACUUUUACCCAUCAGGUAGCUGUUUAGUCAAUAAUAAACAGCACCAAAACAGGAUUAGCAGAGCUCUUAAAAACAGCCUUAAAUACACACUGAGUUUAGAAAAAUGUAAGAAAAUCAUUGUUUUAAUCUACAAAUUCAUAUGCAGUUGCAGAGAUGCAAAAGAGAUCAGAGUAAGUUAAAGUAGGAAAGGUUUUAUAAAAGUAUUGAUGGCUGUGUCCUCAUCUGCAUUUUUGUUUUUAUGAUAGGGCUGAUAUUUUCAACAACGAAACACCCAAUGUUCAGACCUUACCUCAGUCUAAGAGCUGGCUCCACAGUUGGUAGCAAUGGCCCUGUUAGGCAGACUGUCCCCCUCUUUGGGAAUGGAAAGAAGCCCUGCCUGGAUGCAUGGAGCAGAUGGAUACUGACACCAAGGACAUUCAGAUUUUCUUUCCUAUACCUAUUUUCAUAAAAUUUGGAAAGAAAAACUAUCUGCAGUAUUUUUUUAAAACGACUUCUGCUAUUCUUACUUAGAGAAAUCCAGUGAUAGCACCUCAUGUCUUCAGAGGAGCAAGAAGUUCAAGGAGUUAAAUGUCACAUUCAUACUCAGGUAAUAGAGAAGAAUAAAACACAUCAGGUUUGCUUCAUCUAUCCUAAGUGGUGCUUAGGGGUUCAGAAAAAAUGUUUCAAGUACAGGAAAUUAAUGAGCAAUAUUUACAAUGUAUUUUAAUAAAAGGGAUUUUUCUAGUUAACUCUGAGUUAAGCACGAACUCCUUUCUUUUGUUAAUUGUUGGAAAUACCAUUAAGAUGUAUUUGUCUGUUUUUCUGCAUUGGCAAGUAAAGAACAUAAAACAAA